AACUCGGUGGUGGCCACUGCGCAGACCAGACUUCGCUCGUACUCGUGCGCCUCGCUUCGCUUUUCCUCCGCAACCAUGUCUGACAAACCCGAUAUGGCUGAGAUCGAGAAAUUCGAUAAGUCGAAACUGAAGAAGACAGAGACGCAAGAGAAAAAUCCACUGCCUUCCAAAGAAACGAUUGAACAGGAGAAGCAAGCAGGCGAAUCGUAAUGAGGCGUGCGCCGCCAAUAUGCACUGUACAUUCCACAAGCAUUGCCUUCUUAUUUUACUUCUUUUAGCUGUUUAACUUUGUAAGAUGCAAAGAGGUUGGAUCAAGUUUAAAUGACUGUGCUGCCCCUUUCACAUCAAAGAACUACUGACAACGAAGGCCGCGCCUGCCUUUCCCAUCUGUCUAUCUAUCUGGCUGGCAGGGAAGGAAAGAACUUGCAUGUUGGUGAAGGAAGAAGUGGGGUGGAAGAAGUGGGGUGGGACGACAGUGAAAUCUAGAGUAAAACCAAGCUGGCCCAAGGUGUCCUGCAGGCUGUAAUGCAGUUUAAUCAGAGUGCCAUUUUUUUUUUUGUUCAAAUGAUUUUAAUUAUUGGAAUGCACAAUUUUUUUAAUAUGCAAAUAAAAAGUUUAAAAA